AGGCCAGGCCAGAAGGACCAGGGACUACAAACUCACCUUCAGGGCUCCUAAGCUGCUGCGGAGCUAGACGGCGGGCUGUGGGUGGGGAGGAGACUAGAAUAUUCUGAGACGGGGUCAGGUGGGAGUUGGGAGAGGUAACUUGGAGUUGCUGCCCAAGAUGCAGCUCAGCUCCAGUGGCCACACCAAGACGGUUUAAGACAGAGCGGAACCAGGGAGGUUGUUUUUGGUGGCUGGGGGCUUGGGUUUGAGUUCCUUGAACAGCAGAAGGUGCUUGGAUUUAGGGAGGUGAGGCUGGGAAGGGUUCGGGUAUGAGAAAGGAAGCUGAAGUUCCCUGGCGUGGGUGGCAGGAAGGGCUCUAACCCUGGGGCGGGGUGUGAGGGCCGUGGCCGUCAUGGCUGUCGAGGCCGAAGGAGAGGGAUUCUGAACUCGGGACCCAGGGCUUGGGAUGGGGUAUGAAAUCUAUGUCUUGGGUAUGCCUCCUCCCCCAAUCUUGCUCAGGCUCUAAUUGCCUGGACGAAGAACCCCGAGCUGUCUGGCCGGCCUUUCACAGUAUCCGACCGGGGCGUCCUGGACCGCCGCCAGCUCUAUCUGACCACCUCGGCGCGGGACUUUCGGUUCUAUCCCAAGUAAGCCGGGCUCUCGCUCGGCACCGCCUCCUGCACAGCCCCCGCCGUGGCCGGUGCACGCCGAGCCCCUGGGCUGGCUCCCAUUCCCUGAGCCGGUGGUCUCAGCCUCGACUUCUGUAGCAGCAAGAACCAAAGUUCAGGCCUCAGCCCCUCCCUUUUUUUUUUAAGCACCCAGGAGUCCUUAGUGUCACCUCUCAGGAACCGCGGUAGGGACAGGAAGCCUGCACAGCGGCUCGAGGGGAUUCCGGAUCUGAGGGCAGGGCCUCCUUCGGUACUUGAGCCCCCAGAUACUCCUUCCCAAGGAAGCGAAAGUCCCCUUUUACUUCCCUAGGAUGCGAAAGCUCAGUUUCCAGGACGUUAAGUACCUCGAGGACCCAGGAACGCAGGCAACGCGUGCCGGGUCGCGUCCUUCCUAAGGGGUGCUCGCCUGGAAAUGCAGGAGUUUGAAUGUGCAGACUCCUUAGAUCCCGAGGUCUGAAACUCGUCCCCAAGGAUCCAGCUGUAUCCUCACCAUCCCGCCCUGCUCCCACAGGACGGAGCUGUCCGGAUACCCCCGCAAGGACUCCCUGACCUACUGGAGCUUCGAAGAGACGCCCCAGGUCUGGAGCCACGGCCCGCAGCGGCCGCCCUGUCCGCGCUCCUCCCGGCCGCCCCGACCACCGCGGGUCCGCGUGCCGCGCGUCAGCCCGGUGACCUCGGCCAUGCCGCACCGGGGAGCCCUGUCUCUGGCUCAGGAGUCCUACAGCCCCCUGCUGCACCCGCUCCGGCGGCUCGACCGCUUCUGCCCGCUGGAGGCGCCCUGGGGCGGCCCGCACUGGAAGCCCCUGCGGGGCAUCUACAGCGUGCCGAAAGCCUACAGUACCGAGAACUCCAGCUAUGGCAGCUUGAAGCCGGCGCUGGUGUGAGCCGUCAGGGCCAGCCCCACCCCAGACCCGCCCCCAGGGCCGCGCUGCCGAGCGGAGCUCGGGACCUCCGCUCACUAGGAAGGGUUCCGGACCCAGCCUGAGUCGCACUCAUUACGUCUAUUGGCAACGUGGGGGCGGGACUAGCCCAGACACCCACUCAGCUGCGGCAUCACGGAGAGGGGACUAAGUCCAGAUAAUGUCCUUGCAGGCUGUGGCCCCGGGGGCAAGACACGCACCCUGCGGGCGUAUUAAAUAAUGAGUUAAAUCACCUGAACCACACCCACUUCCGGGGACGCUCCGGGCAUCCUGGCUUGAGGGUAGGGUGGGCGGAGGUCCCUAAGGGAGAGGUGGGGCUCGGGCUUAAUCCCUCCUUGGGGGCAUCUGGGUCAAGUGGCUUCCCUGGCAGCACAGUCACGGGGAGACCCUCUCUCACUGGGCAGAAGCUAAGUCCGAAGCAGCGCCCCUCCUGUUAGGUUGGACUGUGGUGCAGGAAAGCCUCAAGUGGAGGGUUGAGGCUUCAGUCCAGCACCUUUCUCGGGUCAUGGCCUCCUCCUGGCUCCCAAGACCCCACAAUUGGCAGAGGCAGGCCUUCCUACACCCUACUCCCUGUGCCUCCAGGCUCGACUAGUCCCUAGCACUCGACAACUGGGUCUCUGAGGUCACUUCACCGUGGUCUCUGCCUCACCUCUGGCGCUAGACCACUGAGGGGAGAGGGCUGGGGCGCUCUGCUGAGCCACUCCUGCGCCUCCCUGGCCAUGUGCACCUCUCGCCCCCGGGGGGAUUAGUGUCCAGGUUACCCCAGCAUCCUAUCACCUCCUGGUGGCCUUGCCGCCCCCACAACCCCGAGGUAUAUAGCCAGAUACACGAGGCAGGGGAUGCACCAAGGAUGGAGAUGCUCCAGGUAAGACUACAGGGCCCCUGGGCACCUUCCACCUCCUUCCAGGCCAUCACUGGCAUGAGAAGGGGCAGACCCGUGUGAGCUGUGGAAGGAGGCCUCUUUCUGGAGGGGCAUGACCCCCAGUAAGCUUCAGGUGGGGCAGUUCCUGAGGGUGGGGAUCUGAAAUGUUGGGGCAUCUCAGGUCCUCUGGGCUGUGGGGUGGGCUCUGAAAGGCAGGUGUCCGGGUGGUGGGUCCUGAAUAGGAGAUGCCGGGAAGGGUCUCUGGGUCUUUGUGGGUGGUGUACCACGCGGGAUGGGAAGGCCAGGACUCGGGGCUGCGGUCUCAGACCUGGGUGAAGCAGUGUCCUUGUCCCAGGGGCUGCUGCUGUUGCUGCUGCUGAGCAUGGGCGGGGCAUGGGCAUCCAGGGAGCCGCUUCGGCCAUGGUGCCACCCCAUCAAUGCCAUCCUGGCUGUCGAGAAGGAGGGCUGCCCAGUGUGCAUCACCGUCAACACCACCAUCUGUGCCGGCUACUGCCCCACCAUGAUGCGCGUGCUGCAGGCGGUCCUGCCGCCCCUGCCUCAGGUGGUGUGCACCUACCGUGAUGUGCGCUUCGAGUCCAUCCGGCUCCCUGGCUGCCCGCGUGGUGUGGACCCCGUGGUCUCCUUCCCUGUGGCUCUCAGCUGUCGCUGUGGACCCUGCCGCCGCAGCACCUCUGACUGUGGGGGUCCCAAAGACCACCCCUUGACCUGUGACCACCCCCAACUCUCAGGCCUCCUCUUCCUCUAAAGACCCUCCCCGCAGCCUUCCAAGUCCAUCCCGACUCCUGGAGCCCUGACACCCCGAUCCUCCCACAAUAAAGGCUUCUCAAUCCGCA